ACAGAGGGUGGAAAGGCGAGAGCGGAGCUCCAAGCCCGGCAGCCCGAGAGGAAGAUGAACAGCCCCAGGCCAGAGCCUCUGGCAGAGUGGACCCCGAGCCGCCCCCAGGUAGCCAGGAGCGGCCUCAGCGGCAGCCGCAAACUCCAGUAGCCGCCCGUGCUGCCCGUGGCUGGGGCGGAGGGCAGCCAGAGCUGGGGACCAAGGCUCCGCGCCACCUGCGCGCACAGCCUCACACCUGAACGCUGUCCUCCCGCAGACGAGACCGGCGGGCACUGCAAAGCUGGGACUCGUCUUUGAAGGAAAAAAAAUAGCGAGUAAGAAAUCCAGCACCAUUCUUCACUGACCCAUCCCGCUGCACCUCUUGUUUCCCAAGUUUUUGAAAGCUGGCAACUCUGACCUCGGUGUCCAAAAAUCGACAGCCACUGAGACCGGCUUUGAGAAGCCGAAGAUUUGGCAGUUUCCAGACUGAGCAGGACAAGGUGAAAGCAGGUUGGAGGCGGGUCCAGGACAUCUGAGGGCUGACCCUGGGGGCUCGUGAGGCUGCCACCGCUGCUGCCGCUACAGACCCAGCCUUGCACUCCAAGGCUGCGCACCGCCAGCCACUAUCAUGUCCACUCCCGGGGUCAAUUCGUCCGCCUCCUUGAGCCCCGACCGGCUGAACAGCCCAGUGACCAUCCCGGCGGUGAUGUUCAUCUUCGGGGUGGUGGGCAACCUGGUGGCCAUCGUGGUGCUGUGCAAGUCGCGCAAGGAGCAGAAGGAGACGACCUUCUACACGCUGGUAUGUGGGCUGGCUGUCACCGACCUGUUGGGCACUUUGUUGGUGAGCCCGGUGACCAUCGCCACGUACAUGAAGGGCCAAUGGCCCGGGGGCCAGCCGCUGUGCGAGUACAGCACCUUCAUUCUGCUCUUCUUCAGCCUGUCCGGCCUCAGCAUCAUCUGCGCCAUGAGUGUCGAGCGCUACCUGGCCAUCAACCAUGCCUAUUUCUACAGCCACUACGUGGACAAGCGAUUGGCGGGCCUCACGCUCUUUGCAGUCUAUGCGUCCAACGUGCUCUUUUGCGCGCUGCCCAACAUGGGUCUCGGUAGCUCGCGGCUGCAGUACCCAGACACCUGGUGCUUCAUCGACUGGACCACCAACGUGACGGCGCACGCCGCCUACUCCUACAUGUACGCGGGCUUCAGCUCCUUCCUCAUUCUCGCCACCGUCCUCUGCAACGUGCUUGUGUGCGGCGCGCUGCUCCGCAUGCACCGCCAGUUCAUGCGCCGCACCUCGCUGGGCACCGAGCAGCACCACGCGGCCGCGGCCGCCUCGGUUGCCUCCCGGGGCCACCCCGCUGCCUCCCCAGCCUUGCCGCGCCUCAGCGACUUUCGGCGCCGCCGGAGCUUCCGCCGCAUCGCGGGCGCCGAGAUCCAGAUGGUCAUCUUACUCAUUGCCACCUCCCUGGUGGUGCUCAUCUGCUCCAUCCCGCUCGUGGCCAUCAACCCCAUUUCCCACCAUGGAAGAGAAGGACAGAAGAGAACACCAGUCACUUUUCCUAAGAACGUUUAACCACAGCAACUCUACACACUAAAAUCUGAACAAUUAGACCUCCAGCUGACCUCAGCUUCUACACUCCGAAAUCCAUGGCCACAUAUGCAGCAAGGAUAAAUAUCUCAUGGCUUUUCUCCACAUUAACUGGAAGUAGCAGAAAUAAGAAGACCAGCUCAUUCCCGAGGGGCAUGGGACUCCAAUGAGGGACAACUCUGACUUGACGACUAUCCAAGGUAUUGUCCAACUUUCUUUAGAUAAUAUGACAGCCUAAGACAUUUCCAUCCAACCUUCCCUCCCUCUCCCCUUCACUGGGGGUUAGACAAGCAUAGCUCUCCCAGAUUUACUCAGUUCCCACCCCAUGUCCUCUCAUACAGUGAUUCCCCUAAUGAAAUCUUUGCAUGUUUAAGCCGGUCUUAGCAUAUGCUUCUAGAAGGACCCAGACUAGCAUAACUGUUCAGUAUAUUUUUUAUUUCAGAUAUCGUAUUUUUCAUUUCUAGAUGUUCCUUUUUUUAAUAUAUCUUCCAUUUCACUCCUCAUUAUGUUUGUUUCCCUUUAAUUAUCUGAAUAUAGUUGUAUUACCAUUUUAAUCUCUCUGUCCACUACUUCCAUCAUCUAUGUUAUUUCUGAAUGUUUCUAUUGACUGAUUUGUCUCCUAUUUAUGGGUCACAGUUUCCAACUCUUUGGCAUGUCCAGUAAUUUUUGAUUAGAUGCUGAAUAUUUUAAAUGUUACACUGUUGACUAAAAAUGUUAGGCUCUAUUCUGGCAGGCAGUAAAGUUUGAAAGUAUCAGUUUGAACCCUUCAAAAACUAUUUUUAAAGGUUUUCUAGGGAAGGUCUGAAGUAGCCUUCCCUCUAGGGAUAGUGUAGUCAUUCUACUAAGAAAUAACCCCCUGUGACUCCAGUAAAUAUUUCUGGUGACCAUCAAAGACACUCCAUUCUGAAUGGCUGAAGCUUGAAUAGCUCUCCGCUCUGUAUGAACGCUACGAAUGGUUCAGCUUACAACUUCUCAGUCAUUUUCCCUGGAUUUACAGAAAUUCCCCAAUAGUUGCAUGGCCUAAUGUUCAACAAAGACUCAAAGGGACCUCAUAGACUUCUGGAGCUUUUUCUCUGAGUAGCUUCCUCUUCUCUGGUACUCUACUCUGCAACUUCUAGCUGUGUCAGCCUCUCCAAAGUCCAAUCUCCAUCUCCUCACGCAGCAAGACCACUGUGGUCUAUCUGGUUUCCUCUUCUGUGUGCCCAUUCCCUGGAGACUACCUUCAGGUAGAAAUUAAGGGAGCUCAGCCACGCACGGUAGCUCACACCUGUAAUUCCAGCACUCUGGGUGGCCAAGAACGCCAGAUUACCUGACGUCAGGAGUUCAAGACCAGCCUGGCCAAUAUGGUAAAACCCCAUCUCUACUAAAAUUACAAAAAUUAGCCAGGCGUGGUGGCACACACCUGUAAUCCCAGCUACUCAGGAGGCUGAGGCAGGAGAACCGCUUGAGCCUGGGAGACAGAGGUUACAGUGAGCCGAGAUCAUGCCAAUGCACUCCAGCCUGGGCCAACAGAGCGAGACUCUGUCUCAAAAAAAAGAAAAAAAAGAAAUUAAGGAAGCUUAUAGGGAUCAUCUUGUUUUUGCCCCUUCUCUCAAAGAUAAGAGUCCUAUGCUGACUACUGUCCAAUGGUUGAAAACAGUUUUUUUUUUAUAUCUUUUGUCCAAUUUUCUAGUUGUUUGGGGCCAUCCAGGUCUAGUUCUAGAAACUCUCUCAUGGCUGUCAGUAGAAAUCCAUGCCUACUUUUUAAAGUAUUUUUGUAUCCGUUAUUGGAUUUCAGCCUUAUAAGAACCCCAUGAGGCAAUUGCAAGUGAAGAAAUAUAUAGCCAAUCAAGGACACAGAAUAAUUAGGACUACUAUAAUAGUAAUAAUAAUAAUAACUAAUAUUUAUUGAGUAUUUACUACAUGACAGGCAAUAUAUUAAGUACAUUACAUACGUAAAUUCAUGUCACCAUCACAACAGCAUUGAGGUAGAUAUUUUCUGCAGAAAAGGAAACUUAAACACAGAGAAGCUGAAUAACUUGCCUAAUAUUGCAAAGCUGGUCAACAGCAGAACUAGGAUAAGAAACAAAGCCAUCUGGCACUAAUGCCAGACCAUAAUCACUGUAUUGUAAAAUCUGUUGUUAUUUUCCUAUUGCAUAAACAAAGCCUUCUGUACACAAAACAACAGGGGAAUGGGAAGAGUAAGGGUUAUGAGAAAAAGAAUCCUGCCAUCCUUGUGAGAUUAAAAAAAGAAGAAAAAGAAUAAGACCCAGAAUAGAGCAAUUAUUAUCAAGUGCCAUAUUUUCAUUCGGGAGGAGGGUGAGAAAAUUUUAUUCCCAAAGGUCCUUUGUGGUUUGGGUAUGAAAUAAAAUACAUUCUCAGAAUACUAUAUUCUAAUUUGGAGUUUUUAAACGUAUAUUCUAUAGAUAUCAUGCAGUAAAUGGUAGCUAGCUUAUAAAAACGUUUUUAGCCAUAAUACAGCCAAAAAACAUCACAGCUUUAUAAAUAUUUACUGAGGGCCUAGUAAGUGCCACAAAUUAUUCUAAGAGCUGAAGACACUAUACAAGUUAGAUAAAUUCCUUACUGUCCUGGAGCUUACAUUCUUACAAAAGAAAAACAACAUAUAAACAAAAUAUUCUAAACACACUAAAUAAGUGUAUACAGUAACUUCAAAAAGGGAGAAAUGCUCAAAAACAAAAUGCACUGAUGUGAUAGAAAAAGGGUGAGUACAGGGAUGUUACUUCAGACUGGGUAAUCAGAGAGCAGACUGCUGAGAAAAUGACAAAUGAGCAGAAAUCCAAAGGACAGGAAGACAGGCAGCAGAAAACCAGAGAAAAAAGGUUUUCAGACAGAGUCAUAGCACAAAGUUGUAUAAUAACUAUGUUCAAAAAAAUGAAGAAGGCCCAUCUGGCUAAAAUGUAGUGAAAAUAAGCACAGUUUAAGAUGAAGUUGAUUUGGUAGGCAGGGACUCAGUAUUUUUUUUAAUCUAAUUUAAUUAUUCUUCCUUAUAUUACUUUCAAUCAAGUUUAGUAGCCUCUUAAAUAUUUUUUUGCUGGGCAUGGUGGCUCACACCUGCAAUCUCAGCACUUUGGGAGGCUGAGGCAGGCAGAUCACUUGAGGUCAGGGGUUCAAGACCAGCCUGGCCAACAUGGCGAAAUCCCAUCUCUACUAAGAAUACAAAAAUUAGCUGGGCAUGGUGGCACACACUUGUAAUCCCAGCUACCUGGGAGGCUGAGGCAGGGAGGAUUGCUUAAACCUAGGAGAAGGAGGUUGCAGUGAGCCAAGAUCGCGCCACUGCACUCCAGCCUGGGCAACAGUGCAAGACUCCACCUCAAAAAAAUAUAUAUCUUUGUAGUUAUUUUCUAAAGCAGUAUAUACAUUACUCAAAAAUAAAUGCUAAAGAGCAAAAAAUGUAAUCAUGUUAUAGUGUUCUCCAUCCAAAAUAAAGCAUCCAAUCCCACUGGUUUUAGUGAAAUGACUCAAUGUUUCGACAUACAGGCAGAAAACAAGAGUUAUUGUGUUUGUCUACAAUGCUGAUAUCUCUUCUCUGUCACAGGAAAUUCAGAGGGAAUCCGAUGGCAAUAACAGAACAGCUUUUCCUUCCACACAUUAGUGUGGUUAAAAGUUAAUGAACUUUUAACAGGCAUUUACAGGAGUUCCUAAAGAUGUUUUAUGGAUGUACUCAAAGUAUUCAUAAAUGAGGAGAAUUUACAUUUGGUUUUCUUCUAAGACAGACUAGUCAAUCUUACAGAGUUCUGUGAGAUAAAAAUCUUUAUGCCUAAAAUACCACAAAUGAGAAUUCACAACCUAACAUUAGCUAGUUAAGUUAAUUGAUCUUGAUUGCUAUUUAUUUUCCACCCUUUAUUCCCAAUUUGAGAUGCUAGUAUUUCAUAGCUUAAGCACAUUUUGUUUUAUAUUAAGUUAUAAUAAAAGAUUACACCAGAAUCAAAAAUAAAAACAGACCUAAAAGCUAAUAUAUUGGUUCCUCAACUUUGAUUCAUGUUUACAAAAAUUAUUAACAAGAAAUCUUAUCACCACUCUUACCAGUUUUUUUUUUUUUUUUUUAAGGAACAAAGAAAAAAGUGUGUCUUGCUUAGUAUUAAUUCAUUUUCUUUUAAAUUCUCAAACUCUUCAACACCACAUGGAAGAUACCAGUCAAAGGCACACAGGCCUGAUUUUAGAUUUCUGGAUGAUCUGAAGUGUAUUCUGUCCCAAACAAAGGCCUAUUAGGCUACUAUUCCUGCUGGUCAUACAUAUGUCUUCUAAAAAUCAUGUAUUUAUUCAAAUCAACAAUUCUUAUACUGUCAAGUGUAAUUUUUCUAAUAUAUUUUCUUCACAGAGGACAAUGCUUUAAGAUUUUUAUAAAAAUAUGGCUCUCAACAGAUACCAAACACAGCAAAGAGACAGACAUAGGCACAAUGUCUUUCUAAUGGCUGCACUAACAGAGAUGGCAAUAUAAUAUUAUUUAUCUCCCAAUAUGAUGCAGUAUAAAGCACAAAUGUUACCUACGACAUAUACUUGCCAAAAAUAUUUAGACUCAAUCUCUACACCUAACUUUCAGUUUACAAGAAACACAUGAGAUAGAGGAACAAAUUAAAUGAUACACACAAGGAAGCAAUCAAAUAGAAAAUUGGUCUGGACUCUUCCAAUAGUCAGUGUCAUGGGGGAUAAAAGUAGAAAACCCAAGGAUGCCAAAAGACACUAAAGAGACAUAAUAACCAAAUAUAAUCUGUGAACUCCUUAGAUCCUGGUUUUAAAAACAUGUACUGUAAAAGACAUUUGGGGGAAAACAGGCAAAACCUAAACAUGAACUAAUAUUAGAUAUAAAAUUGUUAAUUUUUGUAGGUUUGAUAAAAGAUAUGUUAGGUAAGAUAAUAUCCUUAUUCUUAGAAAAAACAUGAGGAAUUAGGAGUAGGUGUCAUAAUGUCUGAAACUUACUUUCAAAUAGAUCAGCAAAAACACCCUGUAAAUAUGCAAUUAUGUAUGCCUGUGUGUGUGUAUGUGUAUGCAUGUGUAGAAAGACAGGGAUAAAGCAAAUAUUAAGAAUUGUUGAGUCUAGAUAGAGGAAAUACGAGAUUGUCCUAUUCUUUUGUUUUGUUUUGGAGACAGCGUCUCACUCUGUCACCCAAGCUGGAACCCAAUAGCAGAGUCACACCUCAUCGUAGCCUCAACCACUGGGCUCAAGCAAUCUUCCUGCCUCGGCCUCUCAAAGCACAGAAAUUACAGACACAAGCCACCACACACAGCCAGAAUUUUUUAAAACUGGAACUGGAAUCAUACUAGAUAUACGAUUUAUUUAUUUGUUUAUUUAUUUGACAGGGUCUCACUCUGUAGCCCAGGGUGGAGGGCAGUGGCAAGAUCAUAGCUCACCGCAUCCUCGAACUCCUGGGCUCAAGCGAUCCUCCCACCUUGGCCUCCCAAAGUGCUGGGAUUACUAGUAUAAGCCACUGCACCCAGCCAGUUGUACUAUUCUUUAAUACAGAUUUGAAAUUUUUUCAAAAUAAAAAAGGCCUUUUCCACCAUAGAUUAGAGAUACCAUUCUAUAUUUUCUUCUAUUAAUUGCAUAGUUUUACCUUUCACAAAUUUUUAAUCCCUCCAGGGUCCAUCUUUGUGCAUGGUAUUAGAUACAGACACAGUUUUAUUUUCCUCUAGGUAGUAAUCCAGUUUUCUCAACAGAAUCUACUAAAAAAUUUGUCUUUUCCCCACUGACUAAUGAAAAAUGAUUUUUGGUCCUUCUUAAAAAUCUAAGCAGAAAAAGGAGAAAAGGAAUAAAAAAGUAAGAAAAAGAGGAAAGGAAAAAAGAAAAAAGAAAUGGGUGCAUAUAGGAACAACUUAGCUAAAGAAGGGCUAAAAAUAAAUGAAGCUAUUAUCAACUUCCUGUACAGCAAGUCAUAUUUACUUAAGUAUAUAAGAAGUAAAUGGCAAAGAAUAACUAAAUACCUAUUUUUUUUUAUGUAUGUGCCCUCAAAGCUAUUCAGGAAAUGCCUAAUUUACCUGAUACAUAAUGUUAUAAGCAGAAAGUUUCCAGUGAUAAGACCACCUUUUACUGACCAAUCACUUGAAUUACAUUUUACUUAGCAUUUACUCUUCUUUAGGCACAACAAAAAUGAUGGCAAAGCAGGGACAUAAUUAGCAUCCUGAAAACUAUUUUACAAACUUUCAUUGCAUCCUGAAAACUAUUUUACAAACUUUCAUUUUUCAGGUGACUUUGAAACACCUUAUUUCUUUGAUUAAUUUAGCACCUAGAAUAGAUUUUUAAACAUGAAUUUAUCAAAUUCAUAACUCUUCAUCCCAUUACGGACAGUGAGCUAGAAAAUGUAAGCUCUUCUCCAUAAAAAAAAAACUUUAAAUACAUACCUU